AUCUUUACUCAGGGCACAGAGGGUCUCUGCGGCCGUAGCGGCCGGGGCUGCGGUAGCCACUUUAGAUUUGGGCAAGGACUUUAGAUUCGGGCUCUGUUCUGUUUCCGCCGUCCUGCUUCCUGCCGAGGCUGGCCCAGGCAGCCGCGCUUCGAAGGACGCCGCCGGGAGCUGCGGAGCAUGCGUGGAGUGGCAGUGCUAACGGCUGGUGUCUCGCACUGUUGGCCUGUGAAGGUACGUGAAGCUGAAAGCCUGGAAUGGCUGGAAAGGGGUCAUCAGGCAGGCGGCCCCUGCUGCUGGGGCUGCUGGUGGCCGUAGCCACUGUCCACCUGGUCAUCUGUCCCUACACCAAAGUGGAGGAGAGCUUCAACCUGCAGGCCACACAUGACCUGCUCUACCACUGGCAAGACCUGGAGCAGUACGACCAUCUUGAGUUCCCCGGAGUCGUCCCCAGGACGUUCCUCGGGCCAGUGGUGAUCGCAGUGUUCUCCAGCCCCGCGGUUUACGUGCUUUCGCUGUUAGAAAUGUCCAAGUUUUACUCUCAGCUAAUAGUUAGAGGAGUGCUUGGACUCGGCGUGAUUUUUGGACUCUGGACGUUACAAAAGGAAGUGAGACGGCACUUCGGGGCCAUGGUGGCCACCAUGUUCUGCUGGGUGACGGCCAUGCAGUUCCACCUGAUGUUCUACUGCACGCGGACACUGCCCAAUGUGCUGGCCCUGCCUGUAGUCCUGCUGGCCCUCGCGGCCUGGCUGCGGCACGAGUGGGCCCGCUUCAUCUGGCUGUCAGCCUUCGCCAUCAUCGUGUUCAGGGUGGAGCUGUGCCUGUUCCUGGGCCUCCUGCUGCUGCUGGCCUUGGGCAACCGAAAGGUUUCUGUAGUCAGAGCCCUUCGCCACGCCGUCCCGGCAGGGAUCCUCUGUUUAGGACUGACGGUUGCUGUGGACUCUUAUUUUUGGCGGCAGCUCACUUGGCCGGAAGGAAAGGUGCUUUGGUACAACACUGUCCUGAACAAAAGCUCCAACUGGGGGACCUCCCCGCUGCUGUGGUACUUCUACUCAGCCCUGCCCCGCGGCCUGGGCUGCAGCCUGCUCUUCAUCCCCCUGGGCUUGGUAGACAGAAGGACGCACGCGCCGACGGUGCUGGCACUGGGCUUCAUGGCACUCUACUCCCUCCUGCCACACAAGGAGCUACGCUUCAUCAUCUAUGCCUUCCCCAUGCUCAACAUCACGGCUGCCAGAGGCUGCUCCUACCUGCUGAAUAACUAUAAAAAGUCUUGGCUGUACAAAGCGGGGUCUCUGCUUGUGAUCGGACACCUCGUGGUGAAUGCCGCCUACUCAGCCACGGCCCUGUAUGUGUCCCAUUUCAACUACCCAGGUGGCGUCGCAAUGCAGAGGCUGCACCAGCUGGUGCCCCCCCAGACAGACGUCCUUCUGCACAUUGACGUGGCAGCCGCCCAGACAGGUGUGUCUCGGUUUCUCCAAGUCAACAGCGCCUGGAGGUACGACAAGAGGGAGGAUGUGCAGCCGGGGACAGGCAUGCUGGCAUACACACACAUCCUCAUGGAGGCGGCCCCUGGGCUCCUGGCCCUCUACAGGGACACACACCGGGUCCUGGCCAGCGUCGUGGGGACCACAGGUGUGAGUCUGAACCUGACCCAACUGCCCCCCUUCAACGUCCACCUGCAGACAAAGCUGGUGCUUCUGGAGAGGCUCCCCCGGCCGUCCUGAGGGGGACCAGGCAGCCCUCAGCAGCCACAGGCCUUCCAGGAGCUGUUAUCACUACCAGUUUCUGGCACAAUUCCAGCACAAUUAUGACAAUUCAGAGAAGCAAGUCAAAGGACUGGGCACCUGCCUCUGACAGACACCAGACCAGGUCCAGGGCCUCCUCCACAGCCUCAGCUGGGGCUCUCAGCACCAAAGAACGAGGGGCCCAGGUCUUGUUGGCACCCCGGGAGCCACUGCCCAGGGUGAUGGUGGCCAGCUCAGGGCUUCCUGCGGGUGACUGUCGCCCAGACCAGGUGCCAUUCAUGACUAAUCAGGAGCAGCGGGCUCACCCAGGCACCUGUCUGCCAGGAGGCCACGUGUGUCCUGCCCACCCAGGGGGAGCUGUAUUUUGGCAGCACCCCACGCUUGCUGCCCGAGGGCCUCUUGGGGCACCUAAGACAGCACCCCCUCUCAGGGGAGACCAUGGUGGCCCCGGCCGCACCCCCCCACCCUGGUGCCACCACUGCAACUUUUGUAUUCACAGGCAUCCCAUCUCCAUCACAGAUAAAAUCUUAGGAGAUAAACACAUUCAAAAAGGAAUGAGAUAAAAAGAAUAAGGCAAUAAAUGUUGAUUGGAACCUCUCAAGAUUACAGAAAAUAAUGAGAAUGAAAUUUUAAAAAUGUUUCCUAUGUGAUAGCUUAUCACAGGUGACUAUUCCAGGUGUUAUGGUAAAGGGACAGCUUGGUGCUGUCAGCCUCACUGACCAUGCAUUUAUAAAGCACCAAAGUGCGUGUGAUGCUGCUGGGCACUGGAGAUGGGACCAGGUGCUGCUGCACACGUAUGCACACACCAUGCAUACAUGCACACACACCACACACGCAUGCACACAGUGCACACGUGCACACACCAUGCAUACACACCACACACCGUGCACACGUGCACACACCAUGCAUACACACCACACACAGUGCACACGUGCACAUUACCAUGCAUCCACACACAGUGCACACGUGCACACACUAUGCAUACACAGUGCACACGUGCACACACCAUGCAUACACACCACACACCGUGCACACGUGCACACACCAUGCAUACACACCACACACAGUGCACACGUGCACAUUACCAUGCAUCCACACACAGUGCACACGUGCACACACUAUGCAUACACAGUGCACACGUGCACACACCAUGCAUACACACCACACAGUGCACACGUGCACAUUACCAUGCAUACACAGUGCACACGUGCACACACCAUGCAUACACACCACACACAGUGCACACGUGCACAUUACCAUGCAUACACACAGUGCACGCGUGCACAUUACCAUGCAUACACAGUGCACAUGUGCACACACCAUGCAUACACACCACACAGUGCACACGUGCACACACCAUGCAUACACAGUGCACACGUGCACACACCAUGCAUACACAGUGCACAUGUGCACACACCAUGCAUACACACCACACACCGUGCACACGUGCACACACCAUGCAUACACACCACACACAGUGCACACGUGCACAUUACCAUGCAUCCACACACAGUGCACACGUGCACACUAUGCAUACAGUGCACACAUGCACACACCAUGCAUACACAGUGCACACGUGCACACACCAUGCAUACACACCACACAGUGCACAUGUGCACACACCAUGCAUACACACCACACACAGUGCACACGUGCACACACCAUGCAUACACACCACACACAGUGCACACGUGCACAUUACCAUGCAUACACAGUGCACACGUGCACACACCAUGCAUGCACACCACACACAGUGCACACGUGUACGUUACCAUGCAUACACACAGUGCACGCGUGCACAUUACCAUGCAUACACAGUGCACACGUGCACACACCAUGCAUACACACCACACACAGUGCACACGUGCACAUUACCGUGCAUACACACAGUGCAUGCGUGCACAUUACCAUGCAUACACACAGUGCACACGUGCACACACCAUGAAUACACACCACACACAGUGCACACGUGCACACACCAUGCAUACACACAGUGCACACGUGCACACACCAUGCAUACAUACCACACACAGUGCACACGUGCACAUUACCAUGCAUACACCACGCAUGCACAAUGCACGUGCACACCAUGCAUACACACCACACAUGCAUCCACACACAAUGCACAGAUGCGCACACCAUGCAUACACACCAUACAUGCAUGAUCACACGUGCACACACCAUACAUACCCACCACGCAUGCACACACACAAUGCACAGGUGCACACACCAUGCAUACACACCACACAAUGCAAUCGUGCACACACAAUGCACACGUGCACACACCAUGCAUACACACCACACAAUGCAAUCAUGCACACAAUGCACACGUGCACACACCAUGCAUACAUACCACACAUGCACACACGUGUGCAUAAAGACAUGAUUUCUUCCUGUGCUCUUUGAGAGCUUGUGGCUGUUGCCCAGGUGCCCUGGGGCUGCCUCUCCACCUGAUGCCUCCUGGUUUUCCCAUUGCGUCUGGCGAACAUCUGUGCAGACACUUCCUGACUCCCACAGAGGCCAGAUGGUGAGGGCUGGAGAGCAGGCUUCCUGGCCCCAGCAUCCCACAGACAUGGGCUCCCUCCCCCAUCCAUCCACCUGUGUGUCUCAGGUAUUCACUGGUUAUCCACGCUCGUUUGUUCUCUUUUAUCGCUGGCCACAUGUGGAUUGCCUCCCGACUUCAGUGGUCUGUGAGUCACUCCUGUCUUUAAUUAUCCUGGUGUUCAAAGUGUACGAGAUUUGCUGGCGGGAACCCUGCCAUGCUCUGCCUGUGUGCCGUGCCUCUCCUUCGAGCACCUCCUCAUGACCAGGCAUGGCAGGGCGUCCUCUUGGGCCUCUGGCCUCGGCCAUUGCUCUGUGGGUCUUGGCUCCCUUUGGUGGGGAACAGCGUUAGAGACCGGGAUCUAGACACGAGGUGUGCUCGAUGCCACGGGGUGCCUGAGCUUUAGGCCCUUUCUGUGGACAGGCUAGGGAGGACAGGCAUGCUGCGUGCAGUUGCACACGUACAUAUGUAAUAUGUGUGUACAGAUCUGAAACAGCACAGAACCGUGCCUGGAUUCCGUCCCACCUUGCACGGUUCUCCCCCACCCCCCAUCUCCACCCUGAGGACCCUGGCCCCCAGCAACAGCAGCAUCCUCACGCAUCUGCUAGGGAGUCCAGUGCACGCCUGCUCGAGAGCUCCAGUGCAGCUUUGCCACAGGAUUGCAAAAACAAACCCACCAUGAAGAGGUCGGGAUUGUGUGCAGUUCACUCCCUGCCCACAACUGCGGGUGCCGUCAAGCACUGUGCUCAUGAGUUCCUUGGGUCGGCUUCUCCACCGUCAGUGUAGUGGUGCCUUCGUUGGAAAUACAGCUGGGUUCAUCCUUCCCGUUUGCUUUCAGUCUUGUGCCUCCCACCAUACCCCACACCCCCAUCCUGUUAGGUUUGUAGAGUGUGACCAUCCUUCUAGAUGUCAAAACUGCCCCUGAAGACAGAUGCAGGGAGCCACUCCCUCCUGUACCUCCUCCUCGCUUUUUGGUAAUGAGCAUAAUUGUCUCCUGGUUUAUCUCCCAUGUGUUUAAUUUUGUAAAGAUAAACAUUACACAUAUA